GGGCGAGGAGUCCAGAGAGCCAUGGCCGCCCUGCGUGUCCUGCUGUCCUGCGUCCGCGGCCCGCUGAGGCCCCCGGUUCGCUGUCCCGCCUGGCGUCCCUUCGCCUCGGGUGCUAACUUUGAGUACAUCAUCGCAGAAAAAAGAGGGAAGAAUAACACCGUGGGGUUGAUCCAACUGAACCGCCCCAAGGCCCUCAAUGCACUUUGCGAUGGCCUGAUUGACGAGCUCAACCAGGCCCUGAAGACCUUCGAGGAGGACCCGGCCGUGGGGGCCAUUGUCCUCACCGGCGGGGAUAAGGCCUUUGCAGCUGGAGCUGAUAUCAAGGAAAUGCAGAACCUGAGUUUCCAGGACUGUUACUCCAGCAAGUUCUUGAAGCACUGGGACCACCUCACCCAGGUCAAGAAGCCAGUCAUCGCUGCUGUCAAUGGCUAUGCCUUUGGCGGGGGCUGUGAGCUUGCCAUGAUGUGUGAUAUCAUCUAUGCCGGUGAGAAGGCCCAGUUUGCACAGCCGGAGAUCUUAAUAGGAACCAUCCCAGGUGCGGGCGGCACCCAGAGACUCACCCGUGCUGUUGGGAAGUCGCUGGCGAUGGAGAUGGUCCUCACUGGUGACCGGAUCUCAGCCCAGGACGCCAAGCAAGCAGGUCUUGUCAGCAAGAUUUGUCCUGUUGAGACACUGGUGGAAGAAGCCAUCCAGUGUGCAGAAAAAAUUGCCAGCAAUUCUAAAAUUGUAGUAGCGAUGGCCAAAGAAUCAGUGAAUGCAGCUUUUGAAAUGACAUUAACAGAAGGAAGUAAGUUGGAGAAGAAACUCUUUUAUUCAACCUUUGCCACUGAUGACCGGAAAGAAGGGAUGACCGCGUUUGUGGAAAAGAGAAAGGCCAACUUCAAAGACCAGUGAGAACCAGCUGCCCCUGCUUCACACCUCUGCUUGGAGAGGACAAGUGCAGCCUGUCAGUUUUAGAAGCAAGUAAAUCAUCCUCUUUUCAAGAGCAGUGUCCGUGGUGUGCAGUUCCUCUCCAAUUGCUGCGUGGUCGUGGCCCGACCUCUCACGGCAUGACAGCCUUCGUCACCCAGCCUGUGAGGGUCCUGACUGGAGCACCUUCUAAAUCUAAGAUUCUGCUGAGGAGCCCCCGCUGGUCCCUCUGGGCAUGCUGUGCUCGGACGGAAAGCGGGGCCUGCGGGUCCUUGUGUCCCUGCCGCUGAAGAAUGGGGCUGCUCUGAGGGAAACGCUGUCUGCUGCCUUCAUACAGAUGCUGAUUAAAGUGAUAGCGAUUCAGAUUA